CCCUCCCUUCCUGCGCGCGCGGGGCGGCGAGACAGCGGCGGCGACGGCGCGGAGGCCCCGGGCGCGGCGCAGGCUCCAAAGAAGAAGAAACCAAGGCCCAGAGAGGGAGGCCCAGGUGCAGGGAGCAGGCGAGGGAAGGAUCCGUACAGGGGCCCAACACUACUCCACCAACCGAAGCCCCCAAAAGGAGCCCGGUGAUGCUGCGAAGGCUGUGAACAGGGGAGGCGGCACUGUGGGGGCUGCCGGCAGCCGGGGCUGGGGAGAGACAUGUGGACACGUGGCCUCUAUGGCUCCCGCCUGCCAGAUCCUCCGCUGGGCCCUCGCCCUGGGGCUGGGCCUCAUGUUCGAGGUCACGCACGCCUUCCGGUCUCAAGAUGAGUUCCUGUCCAGUCUGGAGAGCUAUGAGAUCGCCUUCCCCACCCGCGUGGACCACAACGGGGCACUGCUGGCCUUCUCGCCACCUCCUCCCCGGAGGCAGCGCCGCGGCACGGGGGCCACAGCCGAGUCCCGCCUCUUCUACAAAGUGGCCUCGCCCAGCACCCACUUCCUGCUGAACCUGACCCGCAGCUCCCGUCUACUGGCAGGGCACGUCUCCGUGGAGUACUGGACACGGGAGGGCCUGGCCUGGCAGAGGGCGGCCCGGCCCCACUGCCUCUACGCUGGUCACCUGCAGGGCCAGGCCAGCAGCUCCCAUGUGGCCAUCAGCACCUGUGGAGGCCUGCACGGCCUGAUCGUGGCAGACGAGGAAGAGUACCUGAUUGAGCCCCUGCACGGUGGGCCCAAGGGUUCUCGGAGCCCGGAGGAAAGUGGACCACAUGUGGUGUACAAGCGUUCCUCUCUGCGUCACCCCCACCUGGACACAGCCUGUGGAGUGAGAGAUGAGAAACCGUGGAAAGGGCGGCCAUGGUGGCUGCGGACCUUGAAGCCACCGCCUGCCAGGCCCCUGGGGAAUGAAACAGAGCGUGGCCAGCCAGGCCUGAAGCGAUCGGUCAGCCGAGAGCGCUACGUGGAGACCCUGGUGGUGGCUGACAAGAUGAUGGUGGCCUAUCACGGGCGCCGGGAUGUGGAGCAGUAUGUCCUGGCCAUCAUGAACAUUGUUGCCAAACUUUUCCAGGACUCGAGUCUGGGAAGCACCGUUAACAUCCUCGUAACUCGCCUCAUCCUGCUCACGGAGGACCAGCCCACUCUGGAGAUCACCCACCAUGCCGGGAAGUCCCUGGACAGCUUCUGUAAGUGGCAGAAAUCCAUCGUGAACCACAGCGGCCAUGGCAAUGCCAUUCCAGAGAACGGUGUGGCUAACCAUGACACAGCAGUGCUCAUCACACGCUAUGACAUCUGCAUCUACAAGAACAAACCCUGCGGCACACUAGGCCUGGCCCCGGUGGGCGGAAUGUGUGAGCGCGAGAGAAGCUGCAGCGUCAAUGAGGACAUUGGCCUGGCCACAGCGUUCACCAUUGCCCACGAGAUCGGGCACACAUUCGGCAUGAACCAUGACGGCGUGGGAAACAGCUGUGGGGCCCGUGGUCAGGACCCAGCCAAGCUCAUGGCUGCCCACAUUACCAUGAAGACCAACCCAUUCGUGUGGUCAUCCUGCAGCCGUGACUACAUCACCAGCUUUCUAGACUCGGGCCUGGGGCUCUGCCUGAACAACCGGCCCCCCAGACAGGACUUUGUGUACCCGACAGUGGCACCGGGCCAAGCCUACGAUGCAGAUGAGCAAUGCCGCUUUCAGCAUGGAGUCAAAUCGCGUCAGUGUAAAUACGGGGAGGUCUGCAGCGAGCUGUGGUGUCUGAGCAAGAGCAACCGGUGCAUCACCAACAGCAUCCCGGCCGCCGAGGGCACGCUGUGCCAGACGCACACCAUCGACAAGGGGUGGUGCUACAAACGGGUCUGUGUCCCCUUUGGGUCGCGCCCAGAGGGUGUGGACGGAGCCUGGGGGCCGUGGACUCCAUGGGGCGACUGCAGCCGGACCUGUGGCGGCGGCGUGUCCUCUUCUAGCCGUCACUGCGACAGCCCCAGGCCAACCAUCGGGGGCAAGUACUGUCUGGGUGAGAGAAGGCGGCACCGCUCCUGCAACACGGAUGACUGUCCCCCUGGCUCCCAGGACUUCAGAGAAGUGCAGUGUUCUGAAUUUGACAGCAUCCCUUUCCGUGGGAAAUUCUACAAGUGGAAAACGUACCGGGGAGGGGGCGUGAAGGCCUGCUCGCUCACGUGCCUAGCGGAAGGCUUCAACUUCUACACGGAGAGGGCGGCAGCCGUGGUGGACGGGACACCCUGCCGUCCAGACACGGUGGACAUUUGCGUCAGUGGCGAAUGCAAGCACGUGGGCUGCGACCGAGUCCUGGGCUCCGACCUGCGGGAGGACAAGUGCCGAGUGUGUGGCGGUGACGGCAGUGCCUGCGAGACCAUCGAGGGCGUCUUCAGCCCAGCCUCACCUGGGGCCGGGUACGAGGAUGUCGUCUGGAUUCCCAAAGGCUCCGUCCACAUCUUCAUCCAGGAUCUGAACCUCUCUCUCAGUCACUUGGCCCUGAAGGGAGACCAGGAGUCCCUGCUGCUGGAGGGGCUGCCUGGGACCCCCCAGCCCCACCGUCUGCCUCUAGCUGGGACCACCUUUCAACUGCGACAGGGGCCAGACCAGGUCCAGAGCCUCGAAGCCCUGGGACCGAUUAAUGCAUCUCUCAUCGUCAUGGUGCUGGCCCGGACCGAGCUGCCUGCCCUCCGCUACCGCUUCAAUGCCCCCAUCGCCCGUGACUCGCUGCCCCCCUACUCCUGGCACUAUGCGCCCUGGACCAAGUGCUCGGCCCAGUGUGCAGGCGGUAGCCAGGUGCAGGCGGUGGAGUGCCGCAACCAGCUGGACAGCUCCGCGGUCGCCCCCCACUACUGCAGUGCCCACAGCAAGCUGCCCAAAAGGCAGCGCGCCUGCAACACGGAGCCUUGCCCUCCAGACUGGGUUGUAGGGAACUGGUCGCUCUGCAGCCGCAGCUGCGAUGCAGGCGUGCGCAGCCGCUCGGUCGUGUGCCAGCGCCGCGUCUCUGCCGCGGAGGAGAAGGCGCUGGACGACAGCGCAUGCCCGCAGCCGCGCCCACCUGUACUGGAGGCCUGCCACGGCCCCACUUGCCCUCCGGAGUGGGCGGCCCUCGACUGGUCUGAGGUCAGCCGCCCCCUUCCUUCGCGCCCACUGGGAUGCCCAGGUGGGGUGUCCACGGAGACGCCUCUGCGCGGUCUCCAGGUUAGCUGUCCCCUCCUCACUUCGCACUGGGGCAGCACCCUGAGCACGAAACGCCCCUUCCAACUGCAGUGCACCCCCAGCUGCGGGCCGGGCCUCCGCCACCGCGUGGUCCUUUGCAAGAGCGCAGACCACCGCGCCACGCUGCCCCCGGCGCACUGCUCACCCGCCGCCAAGCCACCGGCCACCAUGCGCUGCAACUUGCGCCGCUGCCCCCCGGCCCGCUGGGUGGCUGGCGAGUGGGGUGAGUGCUCUGCACAGUGCGGCGUCGGGCAGCGGCAGCGCUCGGUGCGCUGCACCAGCCACACGGGCCAGGCGUCGCACGAGUGCACGGAGGCCCUGCGGCCGCCCACCACGCAGCAGUGUGAGGCCAAGUGCGACAGCCCAACCCCCGGGGACGGCCCUGAAGAGUGCAAGGAUGUGAACAAGGUCGCCUACUGCCCCCUGGUGCUCAAAUUUCAGUUCUGCAGCCGAGCCUACUUCCGCCAGAUGUGCUGCAAAACCUGCCAUGGCCACUAGGGGGCGCGCGGCACCCGGAGCCACAGCUGGCGGGGUCUCCGCCGCCAGCCCUGCAGCGGGCCGGCCAGAGGGGGCCCCGGGGGGGCGGGAACUGGGAGGGAAGGGUGAGACGGAGCCGGAAGUUAUUUAUUGGGAACCCCUGCAGGGCCCUGGCUGGGGGGAUGGAGAGGGGCUGGCUAUCCCCCCAGAGCCCCUCUUCAGCAUCCGCCCCUUCCAGUUCACAUAGUGAGACCCCCCCUCCAGGGUGGGUCUGGGGAGGGGACAGCUGUUCACCCCAGCACCCUUUGAACCCACCCUUAGGGAGUCCCCAACACUCCCCCCCUCCUUUGAUCGGAAUAUGUACUGUGAAGAGUAGGGGUGGGGAGGUGGUCUGCCGGUGCCCUGCCCCCCAGCACUGCCCUACCCCUCCACUCCGAGCUGGGGGGGAAUCUGUGUCUGCUAUGGGAGGGGGGGGGGUAGCACCACCUCCCUGACACCCUCCCCUGACCUGACUAGGGGGAGGAUCCACCCCAACCUCUGCCCUGCCCGCCCCAGGGGCACCCCGACAUCCAGGCCACCCCCUCAUGGUGCUACAGACCCUGCCCUGGGGCCCACACACUCCUGCCAGGAAGCCCUACAUCAAUAAAGUUCUGUCUUGUGUAGAUUUCUACGAA